GGUCUUUGGGGGUAGGCGGUAGUGGCGGAAGAGGUUCGGCGGCUGAUGGCGGAUCAGGAUCGGAAGCCUGCGUAACUUUCUCCCUUGAUCCGGGAGUCUUUCCACUGGAUUCACAAUGACAUCCUUUCAAGAAGUCCCAUUGCAGACUUCCAACUUUGCCCAUGUCAUCUUUCAAAAUGUGGCCAAGAGUUACCUUCCUAAUGCACACCUGGAAUGUCAUUACACCUUAACUCCAUAUAUUCAUCCACAUCCAAAAGAUUGGGUUGGUAUAUUCAAGGUUGGAUGGAGUACUGCUCGUGAUUAUUACACGUUUUUAUGGUCCCCUAUGCCUGAACAUUAUGUGGAAGGAUCAACAGUCAAUUGUGUACUAGCAUUCCAAGGAUAUUACCUUCCAAAUGAUGAUGGAGAAUUUUAUCAGUUCUGUUACGUUACCCAUAAGGGUGAAAUUCGUGGAGCAAGUACACCUUUCCAGUUUCGAGCUUCUUCUCCAGUUGAAGAGCUGCUUACUAUGGAAGAUGAAGGAAAUUCUGACAUGUUAGUGGUGACCACAAAAGCAGGCCUUCUUGAGUUGAAAAUUGAGAAAACCAUGAAAGAAAAAGAAGAACUGUUAAAGUUAAUUGCCGUUCUGGAAAAAGAAACAGCACAACUUCGAGAACAAGUUGGGAGAAUGGAAAGAGAACUUAACCAUGAGAAAGAAAGAUGUGACCAACUGCAAGCAGAACAAAAGGGUCUUACUGAAGUAACACAAAGCUUAAAAAUGGAAAAUGAAGAGUUUAAGAAGAGGUUCAGUGAUGCUACAUCCAAAGCCCAUCAGCUUGAGGAAGAUAUUGUGUCAGUAACACAUAAAGCAAUUGAAAAAGAAACCGAAUUAGACAGUUUAAAGGACAAACUCAAGAAGGCACAACAUGAAAGAGAACAACUUGAAUGUCAGUUGAAGACAGAGAAGGAUGAAAAGGAACUUUAUAAGGUACAUUUGAAGAAUACAGAAAUAGAAAAUACCAAGCUUAUGUCAGAGGUCCAGACUUUAAAAAAUUUAGAUGGGAACAAAGAAAGCGUGAUUACUCAUUUCAAAGAAGAGAUUGGCAGGCUGCAGUUAUGUUUGGCUGAAAAGGAAAAUCUGCAAAGAACUUUCCUGCUUACAACCUCAAGUAAAGAAGAUACUUGUUUUUUAAAGGAGCAACUUCGUAAAGCAGAGGAACAGGUUCAGGCAACUCGGCAAGAAGUUGUCUUUCUGGCUAAAGAACUCAGUGAUGCUGUCAACGUACGAGACAGAACGAUGGCAGACCUGCAUACUGCACGCUUGGAAAACGAGAAAGUGAAAAAGCAGUUAGCUGAUGCAGUGGCAGAACUUAAACUAAAUGCUAUGAAAAAAGAUCAGGACAAGACUGAUACACUGGAACACGAACUAAGAAGAGAAGUUGAAGAUCUGAAACUCCGUCUUCAGAUGGCUGCAGACCAUUAUAAAGAAAAAUUUAAGGAAUGCCAAAGGCUCCAAAAACAAAUAAACAAACUUUCAGAUCAAUCAGCUAAUAAUAAUAAUGUCUUCACAAAGAAAACGGGGAAUCAGCAGAAAGUGAAUGAUGCUUCAGUAAACACAGACCCAGCCACUUCUGCCUCUACUGUAGAUGUAAAGCCAUCACCUUCUGCAGCAGAGGCAGAUUUUGACAUAGUAACAAAGGGGCAAGUCUGUGAAAUGACCAAAGAAAUUGCUGACAAAACAGAAAAGUAUAAUAAAUGUAAACAACUCUUGCAGGAUGAGAAAGCAAAAUGCAAUAAAUAUGCUGAUGAACUUGCAAAAAUGGAGCUGAAAUGGAAAGAACAAGUGAAAAUUGCUGAAAAUGUAAAACUUGAACUAGCUGAAGUACAGGACAAUUAUAAAGAACUUAAAAGGAGUCUAGAAAAUCCAGCAGAAAGGAAAAUGGAAGGUCAGAAUUCCCAGAGUCCUCAAUGUUUCAAAACAUGCUCAGAGCAAAAUGGUUAUGUUCUCACAUUGUCAAAUGCACAACCAGUUCUGCAAUAUGGUAAUCCUUAUGCAUCUCAGGAAACAAGAGAUGGAGCAGAUGGUGCUUUUUACCCAGAUGAAAUACAAAGGCCACCUGUCAGAGUCCCCUCUUGGGGACUGGAAGACAAUGUUGUCUGCAGCCAGCCUGCUCGAAACUUUAGUCGGCCUGAUGGCUUAGAGGACUCUGAGGAUAGCAAAGAAGAUGAGAAUGUGCCUACUGCUCCUGAUCCUCCAAGUCAACAUUUACGUGGGCAUGGGACAGGCUUUUGCUUUGAUUCCAGCUUUGAUGUUCACAAGAAGUGUCCCCUCUGUGAGUUAAUGUUUCCUCCUAACUAUGAUCAGAGCAAAUUUGAAGAACAUGUUGAAAGUCACUGGAAGGUGUGCCCGAUGUGCAGCGAGCAGUUCCCUCCUGACUAUGACCAGCAGGUGUUUGAAAGGCAUGUGCAGACCCAUUUUGAUCAGAAUGUUCUAAAUUUUGACUAGUUACUUUUUAUUAUGAGUUAAUAUAGUUUAGCAGUAAAAAAAAAAAAAAAAACCACACCUAAAAUAGACCACUGAGGAGACCAUAGAGCGGAUGCUUUCAUGCACCCUUUACUGCACUUUCUGACCAGGAGCUACUUUGAGUUUGGUGUUACUAGGAUCAGGGUCAGUCUUUGGCUUAUCAAUAAAUUUUAAUCUCUGUUAAUCUUACCUGCUUUAAAAAAAAGUUCUUGUGUGUUCGUAUCUUUAUUUAUUCCCUAGUUUGCAGAACUGUCUGAAUAAAGGAUACAAGGAUUAUUUCAAUGUUACUGCACUGAAAAACGUGUAUGUAUUAGUGUGCUAGAUUAUUUAGCAGAAUAUUCACAAGUUUCUGUUGACCUUGUUGAUUGAGCAUGACUACUAAAUAUUAUGUAAUAAAAAGCAUUUGUCAUAACAGUCUUAUGAAGUAGUUCUUCGAAUAUAGAAAGUUCUAUAAUUUAGCCCAUGAAAUGAUAGGUUUUUAAUUUUCAGAAAUGGAGCUGCAUGUAGAAUGAGAUCACAUGCUUUUAUAUGUGAAAUAUUGGUUUUAGCAAUUAACAGAAGGCAUACUUUGCUAAUUUUAUGGCAAAAUUUUAGAAUAACCUGAAUGAUUAUUUUUAAACUAUCUUGAAGUUGUAUGUAUAUAUCUAAUGGGAAAAUGGAACAAGAGAUGUCAGUAUAAUUGUUUUCCUAUUAAAUGAUCUCAUAACAGGGGUGUUUGUGGCAUAAAAAUCAUAGAAUAUAUAUCAGUAUCUUUUUUACAUUUUCCUGAUGAGAAUAUAAAUUUGAAAUAUUCUCAGUAAGUGAUUAAAAGUACAAUACAUAAACCCAAAUCAAAGUAAUGUGUUUCUUCAGUUAUGUCUGUGCUGUAUAGAACUGUCACUAACAUUAAAGAAAGAGGACACAUUUUUCAAGAUCUGUAA